GCAUUUCCAGGCGCUGCUCUCCGUCGCAGAGAACCCUGAGCUCGGCGCGCCGAGAGUCCCAGCAGGGCAAGGGGGCGCGGCGUCCUGGUCCUCGAGCUUGGGAGACAGAUGCGCAUGGGCGUGGGGGCAUGCGGACCUAAGCUCGGGUGAAGCUCUCGGGAAGGGCAAGACUGCGGCGACGAGAUGCGAGCAGAGGAGCCCUGCGCCCCCGGGGCCCCCAGCGCCCUGGGAGCCCAGCGCACGCCGGGCCCCGAGCUGCGCCUGUCCAGCCAGCUGCUGCCCGAGCUCUGUACCUUCGUGGUGCGCGUGCUGUUCUACCUGGGGCCUGUCUACCUAGCUGGCUACCUGGGGCUCAGCAUAACCUGGUUGCUGCUCGGCGCCCUGCUGUGGAUGUGGUGGCGCAGGAACCGCCGCGGGAAGCUUGGGCGCCUGGCCGCCGCCUUCGAAUUCCUUGACAAUGAACGCGAGUUCAUCAGCCGCGAGCUGCGGGGCCAGCACCUGCCAGCCUGGAUCCACUUCCCGGACGUGGAGCGGGUCGAGUGGGCCAACAAGAUCAUCUCUCAGACCUGGCCCUACCUAAGCAUGAUCAUGGAAAGCAAGUUCCGGGAGAAACUUGAGCCCAAGAUCCGAGAGAAGAGCAUCCACCUGAGGACCUUUACCUUUACCAAGCUCUACUUUGGACAGAAGUGUCCCAGGGUCAACGGUGUCAAGGCACACACUAAUACGUGCAACCGAAGACGUGUGACUGUGGACCUGCAGAUCUGCUACAUCGGGGACUGUGAGAUCAGUGUGGAGCUGCAGAAGAUUCAGGCUGGUGUGAACGGGAUCCAGUUGCAGGGCACCCUGCGGGUCAUCCUGGAGCCCCUCCUAGUGGACAAGCCCUUUGUGGGAGCCGUGACUGUGUUCUUCCUUCAGAAGCCGCACCUACAGAUCAACUGGACUGGCCUGACCAACCUGCUGGAUGCGCCGGGAAUCAAUGAUGUGUCAGACAGCUUACUGGAGGACCUCAUUGCCACCCACCUGGUGCUGCCCAACCGUGUGACUGUGCCUGUGAAGAAGGGGCUGGAUCUGACCAACCUGCGCUUCCCUCUGCCCUGUGGGGUGAUCAGAGUGCACUUGCUGGAGGCAGAGCAGCUGGCCCAGAAGGACAACUUUCUGGGGCUCCGAGGCAAGUCAGAUCCCUACGCCAAGGUGAGCAUCGGCCUACAGCAUUUCCGGAGUAGGACCAUCUACAGGAACCUGAACCCCACCUGGAACGAAGUGUUUGAGUUCAUGGUGUACGAAGUCCCUGGACAGGACCUGGAGGUAGACCUGUAUGAUGAGGAUACCGACAGGGAUGACUUCCUGGGCAGCCUGCAGAUCUGCCUUGGAGAUGUCAUGACCAACAGAGUGGUGGAUGAGUGGUUUGUCCUGAAUGACACAACCAGCGGGCGGCUGCACCUGCGGCUGGAGUGGCUUUCAUUGCUUACUGACCAAGAAGUUCUGACUGAGGACCAUGGUGGCCUUUCCACUGCCAUUCUCGUGGUCUUCUUGGAGAGUGCCUGCAACUUGCCGAGAAACCCUUUUGACUACCUGAAUGGUGAAUAUCGAGCCAAAAAACUCUCCAGGUUUGCCAGAAACAAGGUCAGCAAAGACCCUUCUUCCUAUGUCAAACUAUCUGUAGGCAAGAAGACACAUACAAGUAAGACCUGUCCCCACAACAAGGACCCUGUGUGGAGCCAGGUGUUCUCCUUCUUUGUGCACAAUGUGGCCACUGAGCGGCUCCAUCUGAAGGUGCUUGAUGAUGACCAGGAGUGUGCUCUGGGAAUGCUGGAGGUCCCCCUGUGCCAGAUCCUCCCCUAUGCUGACCUCACUCUUGAGCAGCGCUUUCAGCUGGACCACUCAGGCCUGGACAGCCUCAUCUCCAUGAGGCUGGUGCUUCGGUUCCUGCAAGUGGAGGAACGAGAGCUGGGGAGCCCAUACACAGGACCUGAAGCCCUAAAGAAAGGCCCUCUGCUCAUCAAGAAAGUGGCUACCAACCAGGGUCCCAAAGCCCAACCUCAGGAAGAAGGCCCUACAGAUUUGCCAUGUCCCCCAGACCCUGCUUCUGAUACUAAGGACGUAUCCAGGAGUACCACAACCACCACCAGUGCUACCACCGUUGCCACUGAGCCCACAUCCCAAGAGACAGGCCCAGAGCCUAAAGGCAAGGACAGUGCCAAAAGGUUCUGUGAGCCCAUCGGGGAGAAGAAGAGUCCAGCCACCAUCUUCCUGACUGUCCCAGGUCCCCACUCUCCAGGGCCCAUCAAGUCACCCAGACCCAUGAAAUGCCCUGCCUCCCCAUUCGCAUGGCCGCCCAAGAGGCUGGCUCCCAGCAUGUCCUCGCUCAACUCCUUGGCCUCUUCUUGCUUUGACCUGGCAGAUAUCAGCCUCAACAUUGAAGGUGGGGACCUCAGGCGACGGCAGCUGGGUGAGAUUCAGCUCACAGUGCGCUAUGUGUGUCUGCGGCGCUGCCUCAGCGUGCUAAUCAAUGGCUGCAGAAACCUAACACCAUGUACCAGCAGUGGAGCUGAUCCCUACGUCCGUGUCUACUUGUUGCCAGAAAGGAAGUGGGCAUGUCGUAAGAAGACUUCAGUGAAGCGGAAGACCUUGGAACCCCUGUUUGAUGAGACAUUUGAAUUUUUUGUUCCCAUGGAAGAAGUAAAGAAGAGGUCACUAGAUGUUGCAGUGAAAAAUAGUAGGCCACUUGGCUCACACAGAAGAAAGGAGUUAGGAAAAGUACUGAUUGACUUAUCAAAAGAAGAUCUGAUUAAGGGCUUUUCACAAUGGUAUGAGCUGACUCCAAAUGGACAGCCCAGAAGCUGAUGAUGAGAAUUCUUAUCACUCACCUUUAUAUUAAAAUACUUUACAAGACCAAAUAUACUUCUCAUCCCCUCCAACAUUCCUGGACCUCCUCUUCUCUCUUACCAACACCAACACUACCUGCCGUCAGUUUUCUGUCUCUGCCUCUGCCUUCACUGCCACUUUUCUGAAGCAGGGCAACAUUCGAGAACAAAGUUUUGUCAUGUUACUCUUAUUCCAGUUUCCUGCCAUCUGAUUCACAUGCAGAUGUUCUAUUCCAGAGUAGUCCAAAUACUAUGCUCUGCUGACUCAAGUCAUGUCUCAAACCUAUUUCCUCUAUUAAGUAAGUCAGUCAAUCCAUAGUGAAAUGGACUCUUCCUACCGCCUGUAGCAUUUACUGUUGAUACUGAGUAUUUUCCAUUUUAAUAGUUCCCAGCCUUUAUAACACUAAGUUUUAAGAAAUGUUGAUUAGGCAUCUGCUAAGGUUACAUGCUAAGCAGCUACUUAUAUUGUAUUUGGUAUUUAAUUUUGUUUAUUCUCCAGUUGAACAGUAGGGAACAAUUCAAGCUACUUGAAUUGUUUUUCACCCUCACCAUCCAAGACCGUGUUAAGUACAUAGAAGAUGCAUGGUGAAAUUCGUUUCUGCUGAGGUUUCUAUUUUAAAUGGCAAAUUCUCAUAAUAAAAUGGAGCAUUGAUGCCUACCCUGUCUACCUUAUGAUGGCAUUCUAAUUGCCCCCUAAAUAGACAAGUGCCUUGAAAAUGGAGAAGCACCAGAGAAAUAAGGGAAUGUAUCAUAUGUACAUCGAAACAUUAGCAACCCUAAAACAGCUAAUCAAAAUGGCAGAUAAGUGAAAACCUACCCCUCUUCUUCCAAACUUAAACCACAAACAUUUAUUUUAAACGUGGUCAAUUGAACCGUUUUUACCUGUGUCAGGCAACACAGGUAAAUACCUGGUGAUGGUCUGAAGAGGAGUUAAAAUGUUGAAGGGAACCAGAAUUUUAGUACACAGCAGACAGGAGGCAAGGUUAUAUAGGCGCUGUGUGAGGGGCAGGGAGCCUGAAAAGUUGUUAAUACCUUGGCUGCCACUGAGGACAAGAAUUGGUUUUCAGCAGUGGGUGGAAACAAUCAGCUAAUAUGCAGGAGCAUAGGGUCUGAAGUUAACAUCAUCUUGGUACAGAAACCCCCAAACCUAAGACGGAAUGUGAAUAUUGGUUUAGAACCUGGAAGCCUGUGAAGCCUUGAUGGAGGCAACCAUAAAAUUGGCCCCACAGGGUUGCCACUCCCAUCCAGGGCACAUAUGCGACAACUGCAGCAGAUGGCUGUCACUAAAGGGAAACUCACGGGCAAAAAUAAAUUAUGAAACAAAACAAAAACAGACUUUAAAAAAAAUACAAAGUACACAGGAAUAUCAAACUGAAAAAUAGCCAUAGAUAAUAUUUCAGCCAGAAGGAAAAUGUACCAGUAAGGCAGAAAUAGCAUGUGAGAAGCAGUGGAAAGCAAAGAAAUCCAUAAAAUACAUUGGCAAACCUAAGCAAGUUUUGAUGAUGAUUGUUCACAAGAUAUAAACAAAUAACCAAAGAUUUUUGCAAGGGUUCAGAAACAUAGUAGAACUAAAAUGUUAGUACUAACAACUAAGAAGGGGCAGCUAGGCUGAUUAAGAAAGUAAGUAUUCAAGACCAUAUCUUAUUUAGGAAGCUAAAGAUACUCAUCUUAAAAAUAUAACUGUGUCAGUCACUAAUUCAUUACCUCUCAGCUUCAAAUUGACGUCUGUCUCCUUUGCUGCUUUCCCGGCAGGCUGAUGUUUGGCUUUGCCAAUAGGGGGCGAUGGAAGGACACUCUAUAGCAGGAAGAAGGGGCUUUUCUUCUGAUGUUUUCCAUGGCUGCUAGCUAAUUGGCAUACAGAGCUGUUCUCAAUCAAUCACCUAAGUACCCCCACAGUUUACCCUUGGCUCAUGGCCUUCAUGUUUUAUCAGCAGGCAACACCUUUUGGCAAGUUUCUUAGCCACAAGUGGGUUGCAUGGUCCUAUGGCUGCCAGCGGAAAUCUAAAUCUCAGCCUGGUAGGGAGGCACUUAGUUUCUAACUUCCUUUCUUGUUCACUCUCCCUUACCCCUGGGGGUAAGGAUCUGCAUCCUGAAGUUGAUAUUCUGUAUCCCCUAGAGUCCACUUCUACCCCGUUUAGUAGUAAAUACAAGAAUUGCUAACUAGUAAAAGGUGGUUAAGUUUUUCAUGUUUGGUUACCUGUGCAAUGUGGUUUCUGUCUCCUAAGUAUGUAUUCAAAAUUGCAAGAUAACUAUGAAAAUAGAGUAAUAGCAGAAAGCCAAUAAAGUUGAUAUAUACAACUUCCAAAUUAGCAGUGAAGAAGAAAAGGUUAUAAAGAAAAAUCAACCCUGCAAAACGUAGGAGGGGAAAGCAAAGACAUAGUAGACAAUACAAAAGAUGGUCAAGAUACGUCUAAAUAUAUUUGUAAUUACAAUAAACAACACUAUUAAAAUCUAGAAUGUCAAAAGUAAAAAGCAGUUAUAUGCUGUUUAUAAGAGGUUCACAUGAAACAGAAAUGUUGAAAGUAAAAAGAUUAAAAGAUCCAUCCAAGAAUCAUUUAGAUUUCUGUUUAUAUUAAUGGCAGCAAACAAUAUAUUAAGAAACAGAUGCUCCCUAUUGCCACUUCUGUUCAACAAUGUAUUGCAGCCUGAGUAAUAAUAGGGCAAAAAUAGGUACAUCUAACCAAAACUUCUAUGUGCAGAUGAUAUGAUCAUGAGCAUGAAAUCCAAGAUAAUCUAAAUUGCUAGAAUUAACCAGAAAGUCUUCAGCAAGCUUGCUUGAUACAAUGUUAAAAAAACUGUAGUUCUGUUCCCUAAGAGAAAAUAAGUGCAUAAAAAUAUCAAUCUAUAUGAAUACAUUCAACAACCCCUAUAAGAAAACUAAAACUUUUUAAAUAAAUGUUAAACCUAAAAUGGAGAGCUAUGCCACGUUUGAGGUUGGAAAACCCAACAAAUGCCAUUUCUCUCCAAAUUAAUUAUAUGUUUAAUGAAAGCCCAAUAAAUCAACAGGUUGUGUGUGUAACUUGAUAAGCAGAUUCAAUGUACAUGGAACUACAAAAGGUAGAAAGCCGCCUACUCAACGCCAAAGUUCAUUUUCAAGCUGUAAUAACUAAGACAGAAUGGUACUAGUGCAGGGAGCCAACUGGGCCAAAAGAACAGAAAAGAGCCCAGAAACAGACCCAUUCACAUAUACUCAAUUUAUGACAGAGGUAGCACUGUGAACAAAGGGAAAAGAUAGACUUUUCAAUAAAAGGUGCUGGGACAAUUGGAUAUUCAUGUGAGAAAAUACGAAAUGGUCCUUUACUCAUAUCACAUUAAAAAAUCAAUCAACUCCAGGUAUAUUAGACUGUGUAAAGCAAAACUAUACAGCUGUAAGAUAAUAUAGGAGAAUAAUUUCACAACUUGUGACUAAGGCAAGAUUUCAUAACACGCAAAGAGCACUAACUAAAAGACCACACAUCUCUCCGUGAAAAUUAGGUACUUCUGUUCAUAAAAAUAAACUAUAGGCUGGUGCGGUGGCACACACUUUUAGUCCCAACUACUUGGAAGGCCGAGGUGGGAGGGACCACUUGAGCCCAGGUGUUCAAAGGCCAGCCUGGGCAACACAGUGAGAUCCCAUCUUUUUUUUUUUGAGAUGGAGUCUCGCUCUGUCACCCAGGCUGGAGUGCAGUGGCAUGAUCUCAGCUCACUGCAACCUCUGCUUCCUGGGUUCAAGUGAUUCUCCUGCCUCAGCCUCCUCAGUAGCUGGGACUACAGGCACAUGCCACCAUGCCAGGCUAAUUUUUUGUAUUUUUAGCAGAGACAGGGUUUCACUGUGUUAGCCAAGAUGGUCUCGAUCUCCUGACCUCGUGAUCUGCCCGCCUCGGCCUCGCAAAGUGCUGGGAUUACAGGCAUGAGCCACCACGCCCGGCCGAGAUCCCAUCUCUUUAAAAA